GGGCUCUCCUGACGCGCCGGGCGGGACCCUGAGGAGCCAGCUGGCGCAGGCUAUGGGCUGGGCGGCGGUUGAGACAGCGGCGGUAUCGGGAGGGGUAGGUGAGGGUCGCGAGGCUGCGUGAGCAUCUGAGUGAACGCGGUGCUUUUGGGAACGCGGGACGGGCGACCUGUGGCGCCAGGAGCGGGCCGAGGCGUGGCGCACGGAUGCCGUCUGGAUGGGAAGUUACGGUUUACAGCGAAGUCCACCCAGCGUUUCCGAGGUGAAGGCGCCGCGCCAGGCCGGGCGGGCGGUGAGUCCGGGACCCGCGGGUACACAGCUGGGUCGAGCUGCGGCUGUCGCAAGUUUUGUUGCGAGCGACGGAGGGCGAGGCGGGGUGGGGGGUUGGGAGGGCGUGUGUUCCGGCCCCGCCGGGGCUUAAGUUCCAUGCGUUGGAUUCCUCGCUUGCCGCUGCCGCCCGCAGCCCUCCUUGGGCGCUGGGGAAGAAACUCGCUGGCGGGUGUUCUGUGGCAUCUCAGGGGGUGGAGGGACGAGCAGCUUCGGGGGCACGUCCUCGUGUAUCCUGUGGAGGACCCUGACCCCGCACCCCACCCUCGAGGCCAGAAAUCGGUUGCCUCUGGGGACCUGAGAAGCGAGACCACUCGCGCCCCUGACUUGCAAAGUUGGGGUCUUUAUUGGCCUCCGGGAUUCUGCUCCUGGCGGUUUCUCCAGGCUGGUGAUGGGCAAGCCGGGUGUACCAAGUCCAGGAUGCACAUGAGGAGCGUUUGUAGCAGUCACUGAAUCACCUCAUGACUAGCGGGGCAGGCCUCUAAUUCACCGCAGGAUUUCCGGUAGGUUGGAUUGUGGGGUUGGUGUUUGCACUCCAAAGAGUUGCUGUGAUUUCCCUGUAUCUGUCUUUCUGGCUUGUUAGAUCUUCUCAUUUGGCGUCCUUUCUCCGAAGAGUUAACCAAGACGUUUGGCAUGGUUUCCUUGCUUUCCUCCUAUCUUUUGCUGCUAGAGCUGCUUUCGAAAAGAAGUCUUUUCUUGCAGUGGUAUCUUUUCUUUGGGUUACAGUGUUGUUCAUCCUUUCUUUGCCGAAAGAAUGAAUCCCAGUGCUUCACAAGGUUAAAGGAAAGAUCUGCUGGUAGUGUUUAGUCUUUGUUCUGAGCUGAUAUGUGUUAGUAGCUUUUUGUUUUUAAAUUUUAUUAGUAAAAUUUCACCAGUGAACCAGAAGCUCUUUUUUUCUGUUGUGAAAUGCUAGCUUUAAGAUUUCUGAGAACUUUGUGUCAAAGAAAUCUUUGAAAAGUUACUGAAGUAUACAGAGAGGUUCACAAUUUUAAAUGUGCAGGUGGUCCGGGCGCGGUAGAUCACACCUGUAAUCCCAGCACUUUGGGACGCCAAGGUGGGCGGAUCACUUGAGCCCAGGAUUUCCAGACCAGCCUGGGCAACGUGCCAAAACCCUAUCUCUACUAAAAUUACAAAAGUUAGCUGUGUGUGGUGGUGUGUGCCUGUAGUCCCAGCUACCUGGUAGGCUGAGGUGGGAGGAUCACCAGAGCCCAGGAGGUUGAGAUUGCAGUGAGCCGUGAUCAUGGCAGUGCACUCCCGCCUGGGUGGCAGAGUGAGACCCUGUCUCCAAAAAAAAAAAAAAAAAAAAAAAAAAAAAAAAAGUACAGGUAAUGAAUUUUUACCAAGUGAACCACCACAGAUCAAGAAAUAGAACAUUACUAGACUGGGGUAUAUUUGUAGGAGUGGCAUUGUUGGUUUUAGAGGUAUAUGAAUGAUAAAACUUAGUAUUACAUAUUGUUGAACGUUUUCCCAAAGUGGUUGUACCAUUUAGCAGGGAUACUCUGGUUACCCCACAUCCUUGCUGAUGCCUGUCAGUUAAAAAUUAUUUUGCCAUUCUAGUAGGGGUGCAGUAAUGUAUCAGUGUGAUUUCAUUUUGCAUUUUCCUGGUAUUGAGAUUGAGUAUCUUUUAUUGUCAUUUGUGUGUCCUCUUUUGUGAAGUGCCUGUUAAAUCUUUUUAUCCAGUUUUCAUUGAUAUGCUUGUUUUUCUGUUGAUUUGUAAUACUUUUUUCUGGUUAUGUGUCCUUUCUACGAUAUAUAUGUAUUGCAUUUCCCUUUUUUCAAUCUGUAGCUUGCCUUUUCGCUCUUUUAAUGGUGCUUAUUCAUGAAUGGAGAUUCUCUAACUUUUUUUUUCUUUUUGAGACAAGAUCUCACUCUGUUGCCCAGGCUGGAGUGCAGUGGCACAAUCACAGCUGACCGCAACCUUGACCUCCCAAGGCUCAGGUGAUCCUCCUGCCUCAGCCCCCAAGUAGCUGGGACCUACAGGCAAUCUGAAAGCAAAUCCUGUUUAGAUGCAGGCGAAGGUUCCUGGUGACCCAGGCUCUCACCUUACCGUCCCUUACCGUCCUCCUGAGGGUGUCCUGGAGCUUCAGUGCUGUGUGUUCUUGGCCUCCACGCUGGGGCUGCCACCAACUCCCACUGUCCAGGGCUUCCAGUGGACUCUCCGAGGUACUGAUGUAGAAACUUCCCCAUUCGGUGCACCAAGAGCAACCUCACACGGUGUGGGCUGAAUGAAGAGCUGCCAGAUCCCACAGAAAUGUGAUUGAUAACAGUAAAGCCACACUACUCAAGUGCCUGAAAUACCCCUCAUUGUCUUCUUCAGGUGGCAAGGGCUCUGGAACAGCCACAUAAAGCCCUUGAAGAUAAGGAUGGUCAAACAAAAUAAUAUCAUACCUGGAGAAACUCAGAUCUUGGUAAGAUUUACUGGUUGGGAAUCCAAAGUUAAUGCCAAGAAGCAGCCGCCAGUUGGGAUCAAAUGUGAGCCUAUGGAUCAAGGUGCGUACUCAAACACAGAGAGCUUUGUGAAAGAUGCUACCAGUAGUUUUUCCAGGGCAGAGAUGGGUCCUUUAUUUUUCUCUCUAAUCUAGCCCAUAUGCUUAGCUGAGUUUUCUUCGUAUCACUUUAAAUGAUGAUGUCCCUUGUUCAACAAUUUUCUAAACAUUCUUUAGAUAAUAAUUUUAUGGGCAUUCUUUAUUGCAUUAGGCUUAAAUUUAAUGCAUCUUAAGGUUUUAUUGCAAAAUAUUGCCUUGUUUCCUUUUUAAGAUGAUACAGUUUAUAAUAUGCAAAUUUGUUGUCUGUCCCCUCCCUUUAUGUACAUAGAAAAUGAGCAAACAGGUGGCCAUGAAACAGAUAGUCAUAGAAUUGGUUCAGUGGUUGUGAGUGCAGCAACCCAAGAGUGUCUUAUCUGAAAUACCACCAGGAAUGUCUGGACACAGUAGACAAAGGUUUUUCAACUGGACGCCUUAGGAUACAUGCUUCCAAAAACAAAGUAGCCAAAAAGAAACCAGAGUCACAGAAUAUCAGAGCCAGAGGAACAUUUGGAGGUAAUUCAGUACCUCCUCCUUUUCAACCUACAGGGGAGAUAGUGGAAGAGAAGCAGGGAUGGGUCUGCCUUCUGUGCCCACAAUUCAUUGGAGAUUGUUGUGGUGAAGAAUUUCUUUUAUGAUAAAGGAGAAAUAAACUCCCAUCAGCUUUAAUUCAGGCAGGUUUAUUGAAAAGGUGAAGAAGCGUCUUGCAGAAGCAAAGCAUGGCUAAGGCUUGUGGGCUCUGUCUGGACAAAUGAGCAGCCGACAGUGGCUGAUGCUGCCCCUGACUCUGGAGCCGUGCGGUCUGUGGUUCUCUGUGAGCAUCUCUUCUAUUCUCUUGCACCUUCCCUCAGCCUGGCAGUCUCUGUGUACUCUUCAACCCAUAAUUGAGCGAGGCUGUACCAGCCCCAAUGCCAUGUAGCACUUUAUUUCAAAUUAGAAAGGCAUGAAAUAAACUAGCCCUUUAUAAUACAACUGUUGGAACAACAGUUGAAAAUAACAAUAUCUUGACUCCUGGUUGAGUGCUUUACGCUGAGCUUUCUUUUCUGAAUAUGAGCACAGACUUGGGGAUAUUAGUGUCACCUGGCAUUAUUAGCUAGUAUUCUCCUUUUGUUUCCCCAUAACAUCCCCUCCUCCUUCCCACAGAUCCACUCUCCACUCAUUUCCAUCCUGUCUUAUGCCACUUGGGGCUUGUCCCUUCUAGAAUGCAUCCCUGGCUCCCCUGUGUGCACACUUGUAGUUAGGUUUAGCAUUGGGGGCACCCGAUGGAGCCUGGAAGUGAGAGGAAGGUGAGGUCCGUAUUUCUUCCCUCUCCCUCCCUGCUCUGGCACUGAGUAUCUGGCAAUAGCUGCAUCUGUCUAUUACUUCAGUGGCCACUCUUCCACAGCCCCAAUUCUCAGUGGGUCCCAUAGCAUUAUUUACCUUUGUUCCUUUAGCUCCCAUCAAGGAAGACCCAGAGGCAUUCUCCUCACCAAGGCAUUAAGAAAUGCAUGGGUGAGGGGAACAGCGGCGUGCGUGUAAAGGUCCUGUGGCACCUCUCCUCUGCAGGCUGGAGGUCAUGGCGGGAGAUGCUGCAUGGAUUUGUCCUCCCUGCUGUCAGAACAACAGGGUUCUGGAAGAGUAGAGGACAGGCCGUGGGACUUGGCUGUCUAGAGACAAGGCGGGAGGGAUUUCCUUGAGAGGCAGGGACAUGUGGUGGUUACUAAUCAUUGUGAGGUGUCUGGGAUGUAAUGGAUGGGAAAUCUACUAAGAAGUCAACUUAUGUAAUAAUUAGAAAAGCUCUAGUUCUGAGGACAGAGACCUGUUGGAGUCACCAUAGUGGGAAUUUUUGACCUGGCAUCCAGUUCAGAUACCUGGAGCUUCUUGACUGAGGGGAGAUUGGAUCCCUUGGGGAAGAGUGAAGCCUUCAAUGCUGCCACAAGUGUGAUCCGCCCGCCUCAGCCUCCCAAAGUGCUGGGAUUACAGGCGUGAGCCACCAUGCCCGGCCUCUUUUUUAUAUUUAAAAAAUAUCAUUUUAUAUAUUAUCAGGGCAAAAGAGAAAAACCGUAUGAUUACCUUGUCAUACACAGUAAAAGCAUUUGGCAAAAUUGAAAACUUUUUUCAUGAUUUAUAAAAACAAACCCCAGAAAAUGCUCAGCAUGAUGAGAACAGAAGGCAACACUUCCAACCCCAUUAAGGGCAGAUUUGAAGAACCCACAGGUAACAUUAUAUUAAAUGGCAUAAGAUUGAAUGCUUUUCUAUUAAAUCAGAGAAAAAAGUAGAAUACCUGUUGUUACUCUUUUAAUUCAGCAUUAUACUAGAGCUCUAAAUCAAUGCAAUAAAGUAAGAAAAAUUAAUAAAGUAUUGAAAAGAAAGAAUUGAAGCUGUCUUUAUUCACAGAUAAUGACUGUGUUUGUUAACAAUGCUAGAAAUCUACAAAAAUCUACCAGAACUAAUCAGUGAGUUUAGUAGUGUUGCAGAAUGUAAGCUCUCAAUAUAAGUGGUCUUUUGUAUUUCUGUAUAUUAGCAAUGAGCAUUUGGAAAAUGAAAUAAGAAUACAAUUUCAUUUAAAGUAACAUCUAAAUACAUGUUGUGCUUAUAAAUAAAUUCAACAGACUGGGCACCGUGGCUCACACCUGUAAUCUCAGCACUUUGGGAGGCCGAGGUGGGCAGAUCAUGAGGUCAGGAGAUGGAGACCAUCAUGCCUAACAGUGAAACCCCAUCUCUACUAAAAAUACAAAAAAUUAGCUAGGCAUGGUGGCAUGUGCCUGUAGUCCAGCUACUUGGGAGGCUGAGGCAGGAGGAUCACUUGAACCUGGGAGGCAGAGGUUGCAGUGAGCCGAGAUCGCAUCACUGCACUCCAGCCUGGGUAACAGAGCAAGACUCUGUUUCAAAAAAAAAAAAAAAAAAAAAGGAAAGUCAACAAAAUUUAUGUAAGGCCAGUACACCAAAAACUACAAAAAAUUGCUUUGAGAAAUUAUGAAAGAACUAAAUUAGUGGGGAGAUAAACCUUGUCAUGGAUCAGAAGAGUUGUUAUGUUUAAAAAGUCAGUUCUUCGUAAAUUGAUCUCCAGAUCCAAUGCAAUUCUAAUAAUAAUUCCAAGCGGCAUUUUGGUAGAAAUUUACAAGCUGAUUCUACCAUUUAUAUGGUAAUGUCAAUGAUCAAGAAUAAUAAAAUAGCAAUAUUAUAAAAGAAUAAUGGCGAAUGAAUUCACUACCUAUUUCCAGAAUUACUCUACAGCUAUGAAAAUCAAGAUUAUGUGUUUUGUUGAAAAAAAAAAUGGAAUAUAUAUCAGUGGAAGAGAGAAUCCAGAAAUAGAUACUCACAUGUAUGUCUAAUUGAUUCUUAGGACAUAUAUAUAUGUAUACACACACACACACAAACGUGUGUGUGUGUGUGUGUGUGUGUGUGUAUAUAUAUAUAUAUAUAUAUAUUCACCGUUUUGAAGAUUAUCAUCUCCAAAUAGGGAAUAUAUAUAUAUAUAUAUAUAUAUAUACAUAUACAGACACACACAAACACACACACACACAUACAUAUUGCAGUCUGAUAAGAUAAACAGCACAUUGAAACAAUUUCUCAAAAGACUUGAAUAGAUACUUCAGAAAAGAAGAUACAUGAAUGGUCAGUUAGCAUAGGAAAAGAUGCUCCACUGUUUAGUCAUCAGGGAGAUCAAUCAGUGCAACAAUGAGAUACCAGUACAUAUCCAUAAGAAUGGCUAAAAUUAAAAAGGCUGAAAAUAGCACCUGUUGGUGAGGAUAUAAAGCACUUGGAAGUCUUAUACUUGUAGGAAUGAAAAAUGGUAUGGCUCCUUUGAAAAUCUAACAGUUUCUUAAAGGUUAAACAUAACACAAAUCAGAUAGACAGUCAUUCCCUUCCUAGGAAUUUACACACUGUGUCUGCACAAUGAUCUGUAUGUGUGUUUCCAGACCAACCUGAGGGGCGGGCUGCUAUUUCUCGUGGCUCAGUAACAAGACACAGAUGAACUGGGGAGGAAGAGAGUUUUGACUUCUGCAACUGGUUACAGGGAAACGGCCUGGAAAUUAUCACCAGACCAACUCAAAAUUGGAAAGUUUUCCUGAGCUAAUGUACCUUCUAAGCUAUAUGUGUAUGUGGAAGUGUGCAUUCAUCUAAAUACAUAAGUGAUUAACUUCUUUUAAUCUAUAACUAAGUCUGAGUCCUGAAGACCUUCCUCUGGAACCUCAGUUAAAUUCAGUUAAUCUAAAUGGGUCUAGGUGCUGGGGGCCCUUAUCUUGUCUCCUGCUAAAUCACAGAGGUUUGGAGAGUCCCUUCAGAUCUCCAAUAAACUUGUUUGUGGAGGCCUGGGGAGUUUCUUCAGACCCCCAGUAAAACUUAUUUAAUACUAAAUGGCUCCUGUUAAGAAUGCCUUCGUUAUUUCGUCAUGCUUUAAGGCCCAGGAAAAACCUAGGCAAAACUCUUGGUGGGCUUUUGUUACAUUCCAGCCUUUGUAUAAGGGCACUGGCUUCUUUUUUUUUUUUUCCUCUUAAUAUUUAAUUGAACCACUCAGUCGGUACUGAAACAGUUGUUACGGAGGCCUGUGUUAGUGAGACCUGGCCUGCCACGUAUGGAUGUUCAUGAUAGUUUCUUCAUAAUAGCCCAAACGCGGAAUGAUAGAAAUGUCCAAUAACAAGUGAAAGUACAAACAUACAUGGUAUAGCCACACGAAGGAAUACUACUCAGUAUUUACAAGACAUUACAGAUGGAUUUUAAAAUUACAUUGAUGCAUGAAAGAAGGCAACACAAAAGAACACAGGUAUCAUUUCAUUUAUAGAAAAUGGUUAAAAAUGCAAACGGACCUGAAGUGACAGUGGCUCCUUGGGGCUGAGGGUUGAAAGGCUGAUGAACUGCAAAGGGGUACAAGAAACUUUGGGGCAUAGGGAAUUUCCUCUAUCUUGGUUGUGGCAGUAGUUCCGUUAGUGUAUCCAUUUGUAAACGUGCAUUGAAUUACACAUUUUAAAGUGGUGCAGUCUGUUGUACCGAAAUUAUGCCUUUAUAAAGUUGAUUUCAUCAUCUUAAUUUCUCCAUACUAGCAAUUAGCAGCUAGAAAAUGAAAUUCAAUAAAACAUAAUAGAGAUUAAUAGCCAGAAUCAUUACAUGCUUAACAAUACAUGCAAUGAAGCAGGUACAAGGCCCCUAAAAGCAAUUGGUGAGAAAAAUUAAAGAAGGCUAAAUAAAUAUAUAUCAUGUUCAUUGAUUGGAAGACUCAAUUUUGUUAGCAUAUUACAUCAACACAAUUCUGAUUAAUAUUUCUAGUAGGAGAUUUUAGAGAAAUUUGAAAGCUAGUUUCAAAAUGUAUUUGAAAAUCAAAGAACCUAGAAUAAGCAAGUCGGUCUUGAAGAAGCAAUAAGUUGGAGGACUUACUCUGCUAGAUUUCAAACCUGAUUUUAAAGCUACAGUAAUUUUAAAACAGUAGUAAUGGUGUAAGUAUUCAUAAAUAUAUCAAAGUAAAAGAAUACAGAUUCAAACAAUAUGCCCACAUAUGUACAGUUAUUGAUUUUUUUUUAGUAGAAUCUUUUUUAUUCAUAAAAAAUCCAUCAAAACAAAAAAGUUUUCCAGCCACACACAGGAGGGGUAUGGGUGGGGGAAGGUGUCUGUCCAUCUAUCCCUGGCCCCCAGCCCAUGUGGUUUUGGCAGCAAUAAGGUGUGUGGGGUAAUGACCCCUGAAAUUAAAAUGGUGUGUGUAUGUGAAGGAAAGGCGGGCAAAGCUAUGGGGAGCGGUGGAGUGGAAGGAACAAAGGAGGUCAGUACUGGGAACGCUGAAGGUGGGAGGCCAUUUCAUAACAUUACUUGUUGAUGAAAUUGCCAUGAAUACCUUCUUUGCCCAUCAGCAGGCCUAGCGUCUUGGCAGUCAUGGUGACAAUGACGUUGAAGGUGGGGACUCCACCGAUGCUCUUCAUAUGAAGAUCCACGGUCAAUUCCCCAUCCUGCAGCAGUGAGUCCAGGACCACAGUAUAUUUCUGGCCCCCCAGUGUCAGUCCAUUCAUGACAAAGUUUGACCAGUCUUUGCCAACCAGGACACCAACCUCAGCUGGCGUGAUGUUGAGGAAGGUUUUCCCUGGGAUGGCGGCCCAGAUGGAAGACGGUUACCUGGCACGCUGGCCACAAUCUACCUCACUCUUAUCAGAGUCUGCGCUACUGACAGUGCUUUCAGCUCUGAGUUGAGGCACCUCGAACCUUGUUUUUGUGGUGAAGGAUCCUAAAGUGCUGUGGGGAGUGAUCACAUUUUUGACAACAUCCCUGACUCCACCUCUUCUGCCACAAACGUCAGCAUGGUGGUAUCAGCCGGCCCUUUGUCCAGCGAGAAGGCAGAGAUGAACAUUCUAGAAAUCAAUGAGAAAUUGCGCCCCCAGUUGGCAGAGAAGAAACAGCAGUUCAGAAACCUCAAAGAGAAAUGUUUUCUAACUCAACUGGCCGGCUUCCUGGCCAACCGACAGAAGAAAUACAAAUAUGAAGAGUGCAAAGAUCUCAUAAAAUUUAUGCUGAGGAAUGAGCGACAGUUCAAGGAGGAGAAGCUUGCAGAGCAGCUCAAGCAAGCUGAGGAGCUCAGGCAAUAUAAAGUCCUGGUUCACGCUCAGGAACGAGAGCUGACCCAGUUAAGGGAGAAGUUACGGGAAGGGAGAGAUGCCUCCCGCUCAUUGAAUGAGCAUCUCCAGGCCCUCCUCACUCCGGAUGAGCCGGACAAGUCCCAGGGGCAGGACCUCCAAGAACAGCUGGCUGAGGGGUGUAGACUGACACAGCACCUUGUCCAAAAGCUCAGCCCAGAAAAUGACAACGAUGACGAUGAAGAUGUUCAAGUUGAGGUGGCUGAGAAAGUGCAGAAAUCGUCUGCCCCCAGGGAGAUGCAGAAGGCUGAAGAAAAGGAAGUCCCUGAGGACUCACUGGAGGAAUGUGCCAUCACUUGUUCAAAUAGCCAUGGCCCUUAUGACUCCAACCAGCCACAUAAGAAAACCAAAAUCACAUUUGAGGAAGACAAAGUCGACUCAACUCUCAUUGGCUCAUCCUCUCAUGUUGAAUGGGAGGAUGCUGUACACAUUAUUCCAGAAAAUGAAAGUGAUGAUGAGGAAGAGGAAGAAAAAGGGCCAGUGUCUCCCAGGGGCAUGGAUGAAGCUGGAAACCAUCAUUCUCAGCAAACUAUUGCAAGGACAAAAAACCAAAUACCGCAUGUUCUUACUCACAGGAAUCUGCAGGAGUCUGAAGAGGAGGAAGUCCCCCAGGAGUCCUGGGAUGAAGGUUAUUCGACUCUCUCAAUUCCUCCUGAAAUGUUGGCCUCGUACCAGUCUUACAGCAGCACAUUUCACUCAUUAGAGGAACAGCAAGUCUGCAUGGCUGUUGACAUAGGCAGACAUCGGUGGGAUCAAGUGAAAAAGGAGGACCAAGAGGCAACAGGUCCCAGGCUCAGCAGGGAGCUGCUGGAUGAGAAAGAGCCUGAAGUCUUGCAGGACUCACUGGAUAGAUGUUAUUCAACUCCUUCAGGUUGUCUUGAACUGACUGACUCAUGCCAGCCCUACAGAAGUGCCUUUUACGUAUUGGAGCAACAGCGUGUUGGCUUGGCUAUUGACAUGGAUGAAAUUGAAAAGUACCAAGAAGUGGAAGAAGACCAAGACCCAUCAUGCCCCAGGCUCAGCAGGGAGCUGCUGGAUGAGAAAGAGCCUGAAGUCUUGCAGGACUCACUGGAUAGAUGUUAUUCGACUCCUUCAGAUUAUCUUGAACUGCCUGACUUAGGCCAGCCCUACAGCAGUGCUGUUUACUCAUUGGAGGAACAGUACCUUGGCUUGGCUCUUGACGUGGACAGAAUUAAAAAGGACCAAGAAGAGGAAGAAGACCAAGGCCCACCAUGCCCCAGGCUCAGCAGGGAGCUGCUGGAGGUAGUAGAGCCUGAAGUCUUGCAGGACUCACUGGAUAGAUGUUAUUCAACUCCUUCCAGUUGUCUUGAACAGCCUGACUCCUGCCAGCCCUAUGGAAGUUCCUUUUAUGCAUUGGAGGAAAAACAUGUUGGCUUUUCUCUUGACGUGGGAGAAAUUGAAAAGAAGGGGAAGGGGAAGAAAAGAAGGGGAAGAAGAUCAAAGAAGAAAAGAAGAAGGGGAAGAAAAGAAGGGGAAGAUGACAACCCACCAUGCCCCAGGCUCUACGGCGUGCUGAUGGAAGUGGAAGAGCCUGAAGUCUUACAGGACUCACUGGAUAGAUGUUAUUCGACUCCGUCAAUGUACUUUGAACAACCUGACUCAUUCCAGCACUACAGAAGUGUGUUUUACUCAUUUGAGGAAGAGCAUAUCAGCUUCGCCCUUUACGUGGACAAUAGGUUUUUUACUUUGACGGUGACAAGUCUCCACCUGGUGUUCCAGAUGGGAGUCAUAUUCCCACAAUAAGCAGCUCUUACUAAGCCGAGAGAUGUCAUUCCUGCAGGCAGGACCUAUAGGCACGAGAAGAUUUGAAUGAAAGUACAGUUCCAUUUGGAAGCCCAGACAUAGGAUGGGUCAGUGAGCAUGGCUCUAUUCCUAUUCUCAAACCAUGCCAUUGGCAACCUGUGCUCAAUCUGAAGACAAUGGACCCAUGUUAGGUGUGACACGUUCACAUAACUGUGCAGAACAUGCCGGGAGUGAUCAGUCAGACAUUUUAAUUUGAACCACGUAUCUCUGGGUAGCUACAAAAUUCCUCAGGGAUUUCAUUUUGCAGGCAUGUCUCUGAGCUUCUAUACCUGCUCAAGGUCAUUGUCAUCUUUGUGUUUAGCUCAUCCAAAGGUGUUACCCUGGUUUCAAUGAACCUAACCUCAUUCUUUGUGUCUUCAGUGUUGGCUUGUUUUAGCUGAUCCAUCUGUAACACAGGAGGGAUCCUUGGCUGAGGAUUGUAUUUCAGAACCACCAACUGCUCUUGACAAUUGUUAACCCGCUAGGCUCCUUUGGUUAGAGAAGCCACAGUCCUUCAGCCUCCAAUUGGUGUCAGUACUUAGGAAGACCACAGCUAGAUGGACAAACAGCAUUGGGAGGCCUUAGCCCUGCUCCUCUCAAUUCCAUCCUGUAGAGAACAGGAGUCAGGAGCCGCUGGCAGGAGACAGCAUGUCACCCAGGACUCUGCCGGUGCAGAAUAUGAACAAUGCCAUGUUCUUGCAGAAAACACUUAGCCUGAGUUUCAUAGGAGGUAAUCACCAGACAACUGCAGAAUGUAGAACACUGAGCAGGACAACUGACCUGUCUCCUUCACAUAGUCCAUAUCACCACAAAUCACACAACAAAAAGGAGAAGAGAUAUUUUGGGUUCAAAAAAAGUAAAAAGAUAAUGUAGCUGCAUUUCUUUAGUUAUUUUGAACCCCAAAUAUUUCCUCAUCUUUUUGUUGUUGUCAUGGAUGGUGGUGACAUGGACUUGUUUAUAGAGGACAGGUCAGCUGUCUGGCUCAAUGAUCUACAUUCUGAAGUUGUCUGAAAAUGUCUUCAUGAUUAAAUUCAGCCUAAACAUUUUGCCGGGAACACUGCAGAGACAAUGCUGUGAGUUUCCAACCUCAGCCCAUCUGCGGGCAGAGAAGGUCUAGUUUGUCCAUCACCAUUAUGAUAUCAGGACUGGUUACUUGGUUAAGGAGGGGUCUAGGAGAUCUGUCCCUUUUAGAGACACCUUACUUAUAAUGAAGUACUUGGGAAAGCGGUUUUCAAGAGUAUAAAUAUCCUGUAUUCUAAUGAUCAUCCUCUAAACAUUUUAUCAUUUAUUAAUCCUCCCUGCCUGUGUCUAUUAUUAUAUUCAUAUCUCUACACUGCAAAUUUUGGGUCUCAAUUUUUACUGUGCCUUUGUUUUUACUAGUGUCUGCUGUUGCAAAAAGAAGAAAACAUUCUCUGCCUGAGUUUUAAUUUUUGUCCAAAGUUAAUUUUAAUCUAUACAAUUAAAACCUUUUGCCUAUCA